AGAAGCCGAGCUGAGCGGAUCCUCACACGACUGUGAUCCGAUUCUUUCCAGCGGCUUCUGCAACCAAGCGGGUCUUACCCCCGGUCCUCCGCGUCUCCAGUCCUCGCACCUGGAACCCCAACGUCCCCGAGAGUCCCCGAAUCCCCGCUCCCAGGCUACCUAAGAGGAUGAGCGGUGCUCCGACGGCCGGGGCAGCCCUGAUGCUCUGCGCCGCCACCGCCGUGCUACUGAGCGCUCAGGGCGGACCCGUGCAGUCCAAGUCGCCGCGCUUUGCGUCCUGGGACGAGAUGAAUGUCCUGGCGCACGGACUCCUGCAGCUCGGCCAGGGGCUGCGCGAACACGCGGAGCGCACCCGCAGUCAGCUGAGCGCGCUGGAGCGGCGCCUGAGCGCGUGCGGGUCCGCCUGUCAGGGAACCGAGGGGUCCACCGACCUCCCGUUAGCCCCUGAGAGCCGGGUGGACCCUGAGGUCCUUCACAGCCUGCAGACACAACUCAAGGCUCAGAACAGCAGGAUCCAGCAACUCUUCCACAAGGUGGCCCAGCAGCAGCGGCACCUGGAGAAGCAGCACCUGCGAAUUCAGCAUCUGCAAAGCCAGUUUGGCCUCCUGGACCACAAGCACCUAGACCAUGAGGUGGCCAAGCCUGCCCGAAGAAAGAGGCUGCCCGAGAUGGCCCAGCCAGUUGACCCGGCUCACAAUGUCAGCCGCCUGCACCGGCUGCCCAGGGAUUGCCAGGAGCUGUUCCAGGUUGGGGAGAGGCAGAGUGGACUAUUUGAAAUCCAGCCUCAGGGGUCUCCGCCAUUUUUGGUGAACUGCAAGAUGACCUCAGAUGGAGGCUGGACAGUAAUUCAGAGGCGCCACGAUGGCUCAGUGGACUUCAACCGGCCCUGGGAAGCCUACAAGGCGGGGUUUGGGGAUCCCCACGGCGAGUUCUGGCUGGGUCUGGAGAAGGUGCAUAGCAUCACGGGGGACCGCAACAGCCGCCUGGCCGUGCAGCUGCGGGACUGGGAUGGCAACGCCGAGUUGCUGCAGUUCUCCGUGCACCUGGGUGGCGAGGACACGGCCUAUAGCCUGCAGCUCACUGCACCCGUGGCCGGCCAGCUGGGCGCCACCACCGUCCCACCCAGCGGCCUCUCCGUACCCUUCUCCACUUGGGACCAGGAUCACGACCUCCGCAGGGACAAGAACUGCGCCAAGAGCCUCUCUGCCCCAUCGGUGGCUCAAAGACCUGACCAUGUUCCCUCUCCCCUGACCCCGGCAGGAGGCUGGUGGUUUGGCACCUGCAGCCAUUCCAACCUCAACGGCCAGUACUUCCGCUCCAUCCCACAGCAGCGGCAGAAGCUUAAGAAGGGAAUCUUCUGGAAGACCUGGCGGGGCCGCUACUACCCGCUGCAGGCCACCACCAUGUUGAUCCAGCCCAUGGCAGCAGAGGCAGCCUCCUAGCGUCCUGGCUGGGCCUGGUCCCAGGCCCACGAAAGACGGUGACUCUUGGCUCUGCCCGAGGAUGUGGCCGUUCCCUGCCUGGGCAGGGGCUCCAAGGAGGGGCCAUCUGGAAACUUGUGGACAGAGAAGAAGACCACGACUGGAGAAGCCCCCUUUCUGAGUGCAGGGGGGCUGCAUGCGUUGCCUCCUGAGAUCGAGGCUGCAGGAUAUGCUCAGACUCUAGAGGCGUGGACCAAGGGGCAUGGAGCUUCACUCCUUGCUGGCCAGGGAGUUGGGGACUCAGAGGGACCACUUGGGGCCAGCCAGACUGGCCUCAAUGGCGGACUCAGUCACAUUGACUGACGGGGACCAGGGCUUGUGUGGGUCGAGAGCGCCCUCAUGGUGCUGGUGCUGUUGUGUGUAGGUCCCCUGGGGACACAAGCAGGCGCCAAUGGUAUCUGGGCGGAGCUCACAGAGUUCUUGGAAUAAAAGCAACCUCAGAACA